AGCGCGCGCCCUGCGCUCGGGACCAGGCUGGAGCCGCGCGUGCAGCUCGCAGGGAGCCAGCCGGGGCGUCCGGAGUCGCGGCCGCAGCGCGGAGCUGGCAGGGGUGCCCGCCUGGGCACGCAGUCGCCUCCCCGGGGGCCUCCCGGGCUUCUCAGCGCCCGCCUCGCCCGCCCAGCCACACCAGGCGCCACCGCCGUGGCCUGGGCAUGAGCGGCCGCCGCUAGCUGCGCCCUGCCCGGGUCGGACGCCCGCCCGCCCCGUCACGUGCGCCCAAGUCCUCGCGGCCGGGGCAGCGCGGUUCCCAUGCUUCAAGGUAAGGGCCGAGCGGGCCGCGGGUCACGGGGUGUGGGGCAGAAGACGCAGGCUGGAAAGCUCCAGCUAGGUGCCCACUCGUCCAGAGUGCCCACUGCAGCCUGCCCCGGCUGCCUCGCACCAGGUCCCCUGACCCAGCUGGCGUCACCCAUCCCCUGGCUUCCACCCUCAAAGCGCAUCCCCGAGGAGGAGACUGAGACCCAGGUGGGCACGAGGGCCUAAGGGAGAGGUGGGGGACCCACUUUAGGAAGGGGGGCUUCAUUUCCCUCGGAACAGUGGCCUGGGGGCAGGGGGCAGUGGGGAGGGAAAGUUUCCCAGAAGAGCCCUCUGGAAACCUGGCCGCCUUCUCUCCCUGCCAGGAGCUAAGACUUUUUCAUUUGCUGAGCUUUGCCUUCUUCCAGAGUCGGUGCUGCAUUUUCAUCCCAUCCCAUUCACCCAACACCCACGAGAAAGGGGCAUUGGCCCCAUUUCACAGAUGCAGAAACUGAGUCUCCGAGAGGUUUGGUCUCUUGCCCACGAUCACAGAGUGGGGAAGUGGUGGAGAUGGCCUCAAACACGCCGGCCUCUGUCACCACCACCUCACACCUUUGUCUGUUAGGAAUCUCUGCUUCAUUGACAGGUGGGGGGUUGCCUAACUGACACUAGGUUUCCUCAGCCAGAAAAGAAAAGACUCUACACACCAAAAACCCAAGAGAUAUUCAACAUGGGUCCUCAGGGCUCCACUGUCUCACCCCACUCGUGUCCUGUCCUCCCGCAGCCACGGACUGCCUGGGCACAAGUGGUCCUGCCAGUGUGUGUCCCGUAGCAACCCCGAUGGCUCUGAGACAAGAAACUCAAGGGUCAAGUUCAUGGAACCUUCUGCAGGAAUUGAGAGUGAAGUGGAGGUGACCAGGGCUCUACCCACCUGAGCAGGCUGUUGAUGGAGAAGGGGGCGGAUGACAGCCGGGACCGUGGUCAUCACCGGGGGCAUCUUGGCGACUGUGAUUUUGCUCUGCAUCAUCGCUGUUCUGUGCUACUGCCGGCUCCAGUACUACUGCUGCAAGAAGGACGAGUCGGAGGAGGACGAGGAGGAACCAGACUUCGCCGUUCACUCGCACCUGCCCCCGCUGCACUCCAACCGCAACCUGGUGCUGACCAACGGGCCGGCGCUCUACCCCACCGCCUCCACCUCCUUCAGCCAGAAGUCCCCGCAGGCCCGCGCCCUCUGCCGCAGCUGCUCCCACUGCGAGCCCCCCACCUUCUUCCUGCAGGAGCCGCCGGAGGAGGAAGAGGACGUGCUGAACGGCGGGGAGCGCGUGCUCUACAAGAGCGUGAGCCAGGAGGACGUGGAGCUGCCCCCGGGGGGCUUCGGGGGCCUGCAGGCGCUCAACCCCAACCGCCUCUCAGCCAUGCGGGAGGCCUUCGCCAGGAGCCGCAGCAUCAGCACCGACGUGUGACCUGGGCCCGCCCCCGGGAUCCUGGCCUUGAAGGUCCUGAGACAAUGGGGGGAUUCCUUUGGCACACCCACCUGGCCCCAGGCCCCAAGUGGGGCUUGGCUGAGCCCUCCUGGAAUCCCUGUCCUCAGGGGAGGCCCAGGCUUGGGGAGCCCCCAGGCUCGUGGCAGGGAUAAGGCUCAUUGAACACAAAUGUGUCCUGGGGGGAGGCACAGCUGGGGCCUGGGGCUAGAAGGACCAGGUGACCAUACAGCCGGCUGGGCAUGCACCAGGGCUCUCAGGCACAGAGGCCACCGUUACUCCUGAUGAUUCUGUCUCAGACCCAACAACCUGGCCUUCCCAGGAGGUCUCCAUGUGUCACCCCCUCCCUGGGUCUCACCCUUCUCACCUGCUCAAGGAAGGGAUGACCUCAGUGAGGCCCAGGGCCCUGCAGCAAGGCCCUCCCUGGCAAUUGCAGACCAAGGAUUCUGCUCCUCCACCUUGAACUCCAGCCUCUUUCUCUCCAUUUUUCCCUCUCUCUCCCCUACCCGUCUCUCCCUCUCUCUCACACACACACUCUUCCGGGUUCAAGGGCCAAGUGUCUGCCUAGGCUGAGACACGUGCUGAGCUCCCUGAAGAUGGACCAGCUGCCCCCUAGAAGGGAGACUUUCAGGGGCAUCAGGGCCCUUGGGAUGCUCCGCCCUGACCAGCUUUUUGGUGGCAGAGGGAGGCACGGGGAGAGGGAGAGGCCAUGUCGCAGUCCCCCUGCCGUGGGAGAGGCAACGUGGAAAUGUAUAGACCCAGUGCUCAGCCAGAAACAGGGCCAGCAAGCGGCAGUGAACGGAGGCAGCCCGGGGCUCGUCAGGGGCAGAGCCAUGGCCCAGGGGUUGAAAACCCCCGAGUUCCCCGUGAGACUUGGCUGGCCCUUCCCACCCCUGGGCCUCAGUCUCCCCAUCUUGUGUGAUGAGGAGAGACCCUGAGGACAGAGGUCUUCAGGCUGUGGGUCUCAACAGGAACUGAGAUCCCCAAGGGAGACAGAGUUGCAGGUCACCUCCCCUACCUGCUUCUCAGCAGGACCUAGGAGGCCUGGCCCAGCUCCUGGUGGACCCCAAGCAGCCAGAGCCUACUGCUGCCAUCUGAAGACCUCAUCUGAGCCCACUUUCCACCAAGCGCCCACCCAGGCUGAGGUCUCCUGGGAAUUCUCACCCGCUCUCCUGCUGCUAAGGAAAUGACGUCAAUGGCUACCCCAGAGAAAUGCCCCACAUCCCAGGACACCAGCCAUCAGGAAGGCAGCUCUUCCUCACCCAGAAAGAGGCAAUUAUUUCCUCUCAGCAGCCUGGCCCCAGGAGCCCCCUUCCCUCUCUGGGGCUCUGCCUCUCCUUUUGUGCCCUGCCAUGGAGCCCCAGGGCCGGGGCAGCCCCUCUCUGCCCAGGGAAGGCACCGCCCUCAAAGACAAGGCUUGGCCGGGCAGUGACCUUCCCUGAGCGGAGGGGUGGCUUGAGCAGGACACUUCUUGCCCUUACUCAAAAACGAAAUGGCCAGUUUCCAGAGGCGUCGGGGGAACGGCUGACGAAGUCACAAUCGUUAUGUUCUCAAUUGUUUUCCUCCUCUUACUUUCUCUCCUGCCUCGUUUGGACAGGCCAGUGGCAUUCGCCCUUGAGGUCCCUCGCAGCCCCGGCCCCCCGGGCCCGCCCACACCUCUGGCUUCCUCUGUGCAUCCUGUGAAGUCUGUUUCUGAUGCGUUGGCGUGGGGGGUGGGCUGGGUGGGGUGGGGAUGAGGGCCCAGCCCUCAUGAUUCCAUUUCCCAAUUCCUUUCUGGUCUCCAUCCUCUCUGUAGAUAUGUAGAUCUCUUUGAAACGAAGUAAGCACCCAUCCCUCCCAGCUCACUCGGCUCCACCGUGGGGACCUGCUGGGGGAGCCGCUGGCUCCCUGAGGAAAGUGAAAGCCAAUAAAACAUCUCCCACA